GGGUCGGUAGUUCAGCGCCGGCGCCGGUGUGCGAGCCGCGGCAGAGUGAGGCAGGCAACCCGAGGUGCGGAGCGACCUGCGGAGGCUGAGCCCCGCUUUCUCCCAGGGUUUCUUAUCAGCCAGCCGCCGCUGUCCCCGGGGGAGUAGGAGGCUCCUGACAGGCCGCGGCUGUCUGUGUGUCCUUCUGAGUGUCAGAGGAACGGCCAGACCCCGCGGGCCGGAGCAGAACGCGGCCAGGGCAGAAAGCGGCGGCAGGAGAAGCAGGCAGGGGGCCGGAGGACGCAGACCGAGACCCGAGGCGGAGGCGGACCGCGAGCCGGCCAUGUCGGUGGUGGGGUUGGACGUGGGCUCGCAGAGCUGCUACAUCGCGGUAGCCCGGGCCGGGGGCAUCGAGACCAUCGCCAAUGAGUUCAGCGACCGGUGCACCCCGUCAGUCAUAUCAUUUGGAUCAAAAAAUAGAACAAUCGGAGUUGCAGCCAAAAAUCAGCAAAUCACUCAUGCAAACAAUACGGUGUCUAACUUCAAAAGAUUUCAUGGCCGAGCAUUCAAUGACCCCUUCAUUCAAAAGGAGAAGGAAAACUUGAGUUACGAUUUGGUUCCAUUGAAAAAUGGUGGAGUUGGAAUAAAGGUAAUGUACAUGGGUGAAGAACAUCUAUUUAGUGUGGAGCAGAUAACAGCCAUGUUGUUGACUAAGCUGAAGGAAACUGCUGAAAACAGCCUCAAGAAACCAGUAACAGAUUGUGUUAUUUCAGUCCCCUCCUUCUUUACAGAUGCUGAGAGGCGAUCUGUGUUAGAUGCUGCACAGAUUGUUGGCCUAAACUGUUUAAGACUUAUGAAUGACAUGACAGCUGUUGCUUUGAAUUACGGAAUUUAUAAGCAGGAUCUCCCAAGCCUGGAUGAGAAACCUCGGAUAGUGGUUUUUGUUGAUAUGGGACAUUCAGCUUUUCAAGUGUCUGCUUGUGCUUUUAACAAGGGAAAAUUGAAGGUACUGGGAACAGCUUUUGAUCCUUUCUUAGGAGGAAAAAACUUCGAUGAAAAGUUAGUGGAACAUUUUUGUGCAGAAUUUAAAACUAAGUACAAGUUGGAUGCAAAAUCCAAAAUACGAGCACUCCUACGUCUGUAUCAGGAAUGUGAAAAACUGAAAAAGCUAAUGAGCUCUAACAGCACAGACCUUCCACUGAAUAUCGAAUGCUUUAUGAAUGAUAAAGAUGUUUCCGGAAAGAUGAACAGGUCACAAUUUGAAGAACUCUGUGCUGAACUUCUGCAAAAGAUAGAAGUACCCCUUUAUUCACUGUUGGAACAAACUCAUCUCAAAGUAGAAGAUGUGAGUGCAGUUGAGAUUGUUGGAGGCGCUACACGAAUUCCAGCUGUGAAGGAAAGAAUUGCCAAAUUCUUUGGAAAAGAUAUUAGCACAACACUCAAUGCAGAUGAAGCAGUAGCCAGAGGAUGUGCAUUACAGUGUGCAAUACUUUCCCCGGCAUUUAAAGUUAGAGAAUUUUCCGUCACAGAUGCAGUUCCUUUUCCAAUAUCUCUGAUCUGGAACCAUGAUUCAGAAGAUACUGAAGGUGUUCAUGAAGUCUUUAGUCGAAACCAUGCUGCUCCUUUCUCCAAAGUUCUCACCUUUCUGAGAAGGGGGCCUUUUGAGCUAGAAGCUUUCUAUUCUGAUCCCCAAGGAGUUCCAUAUCCAGAAGCAAAAAUAGGCCGCUUUGUAGUUCAGAAUGUUUCUGCACAGAAAGAUGGAGAAAAAUCUAGAGUAAAAGUCAAAGUGCGAGUCAACACCCAUGGCAUUUUCACCAUCUCUACGGCAUCUAUGGUGGAGAAAGUCCCAACUGAGGAGAAUGAAAUGUCUUCUGAAGCUGACAUGGAGUGUCUGAAUCAGAGACCACCAGAAAACCCAGACACUGAUAAAAAUGUCCAGCAAGACAACAGUGAAGCUGGAACACAGCCCCAGGUACAAACUGAUGCUCAACAAACCUCACAGUCUCCCCCUUCACCUGAACUUACCUCAGAAGAAAACAAAAUCCCAGAUGCUGACAAAGCAAAUGAAAAAAAAGUUGACCAGCCUCCAGAAGCUAAAAAGCCCAAAAUAAAGGUGGUGAAUGUUGAGCUGCCUAUUGAAGCCAACUUGGUCUGGCAGUUAGGGAAAGACCUUCUUAACAUGUAUAUUGAGACAGAGGGUAAGAUGAUAAUGCAAGAUAAAUUGGAAAAAGAAAGGAAUGAUGCUAAAAAUGCAGUUGAGGAAUAUGUGUAUGAGUUCAGAGACAAGCUGUGUGGACCAUAUGAAAAAUUUAUAUGUGAGCAGGAUCAUCAAAAUUUUUUGAGACUCCUCACAGAAACUGAAGACUGGCUGUAUGAAGAAGGAGAGGACCAAGCUAAACAAGCAUAUGUUGACAAGUUGGAAGAAUUAAUGAAAAUUGGCACUCCAGUUAAAGUUCGGUUUCAGGAAGCUGAAGAACGGCCAAAAAUGUUUGAAGAACUAGGACAGAGGCUGCAGCAUUAUGCCAAGAUAGCAGCUGACUUCAGAAAUAAGGAUGAGAAAUACAACCAUAUUGAUGAGUCUGAAAUGAAAAAAGUGGAGAAGUCUGUUAAUGAAGUGAUGGAAUGGAUGAAUAAUGUCAUGAAUGCUCAGGCUAAAAAGAGUCUUGAUCAGGAUCCAGUUGUACGUGCUCAGGAAAUUAAAACAAAAAUCAAGGAAUUGAACAACACAUGUGAACCCGUUGUAACACAACCGAAACCAAAAAUUGAAUCACCCAAACUGGAAAGAACUCCAAAUGGCCCAAAUAUUGAUAAAAAGGAAGAAGAUUUAGAAGACAAAAACAAUUUUGGUGCUGAACCUCCACAUCAGAAUGGUGAAUGUUACCCUAAUGAGAAAAAUUCUGUUAAUAUGGACUUGGACUAGAUAACCUUAAAUUGGCCUAUUCCUUCAAUUAAUAAAAUAUUUUUGCCAUAGUAUGUGACUCUACAUAACAUACUGAAACUAUUUAUAUUUUCUUUUUUAAGGAUAUUUAGAAAUUUUGUGUAUUAUAUGGAAAAAGAAAAAAAGCUUAAGUCUGUAGUCUUUAUGAUCCUAAAAGGGAAAAUUGCCUUGGUAACUUUCAGAUUCCUGUGGAAUUGUGAAUUCAUACUAAGCUUUCUGUGCAGUCUCACCAUUUGCAUCACUGAGGAUGAAACUGACUUUUGUCUUUUGGAGAAAAAAAACUGUACUGCUUGUUCAAGAGGGCUGUGAUUAAAAUCUUUAAGCAUUUGUUCCUGCCAAGGUAGUUUUCUUGCAUUUUGCUCUCCAUUCAGCAUGUGUGUGGGUGUGGAUGUUUAUAAACAAGACUAAGUCUGACUUCAUAAGGGCUUUCUAAAACCAUUUCUGUCCAAGAGAAAAUGACUUUUUGCUUUGAUAUUAAAAAUUCAAUGAGUAAAACAAAAGCUAGUCAAAUGUGUUAGCAGCAUGCAGAACAAAAACUUUAAACUUUCUCUCUCACUAUACAGUAUAUUGUCAUGUGAAAGUGUGGAAUGGAAGAAAUGUCGAUCCUGUUGUAACUGAUUGUGAACACUUUUAUGAGCUUUAAAAUAAAGUUCAUCUUAUGGUGUCAUUUCUAAACUGUUGAUUUUGUCACUAAUUUAAAAAAUGAGAUGAGGGAGAAUAUGAAUUAUUCUAGCAGAAAUGAAGUUAGUGUCCAGUUUUUCUUUUUUACUGCUUAUGUUCUCUCUUUUCUAAGUGAAAAUGUUUUUCUCCUGACAGAAAAAUAGCAUAUGUUUAUUACAUUAAAGCAUUUUAAAAAUACUAUAAAGUGAAUAAAACUUAAAAUCUUGCCACCCAGAAGAAAACAUUGUUAACACUUCGUUAUACAUCCUUGGAGCCUUUUACCCCUAAUGAUGGGGGUAUAUUUGUGUGAGUGUCUAUGUUAUAGUGCUGUAGGCUGUUUUUAAAAACUCUGUGCCAGGGAAAUUAGUAAAUACAGUCAAGUGUUGUAACUGCAUAAAUGUAGUGAGUUCAUUAUAAAGACGUACUUAAAAAUACCAAUCUUGCUAUUGGUAGAUUUAGGUGUUUCUCAUUUUUGCUGUUCUAAAUAAUGCUGCAAUGAAUCUAUCUGGUUGUUUUGUAAGCACAAAAUUGAAGUAGUGUUGGAGGUAGGGGAGAAGACACAUGCACUUAGGAUAGGUGACAACCAGCUCCUCACUAGGGUGCAACAGUUUAUUCUUUUUUUUUUUUUGGUAGAGCUGGGGUUUCGCUAUGUUGCCCAAGUUCGUCUUGAACUCCUGGGCUCAAGCAAUCUGUCUGCCUCAGCCUCCCAAAGUGCUGGGAUUACAUGGUGUGAGCCACCAUGCCCAGCCAUUUAUGAUCUUGAUGAGGGCCAACUUUCCCUCUUCCACAAGGGAUUAAUCUUAGAACUAUAGCCAAUUUAUUAUAAGUACUAUUUAGCUACUCUGUGCUCCACACAUCACGGAGUAAUAUCUUCAAACUAUGAGGUUUAGUAACACUUGACUGCUGAGGUUUAUUUCCUCAGCUCUGAUGCUUCCUGGGUGAAGAUGUAAGUUAUUAAAUUAACUCAAAUUUUAAAGCUAACACUUCAUUCCAUCUAGACCAGGUAGCUCGUCAUUUGUACGUCUGAUAGGUGCUUCAACAUCUCAGAAUUGGCUUAUUUUUCAUGCAUUGCAUAUUGUACUCAUUUGUAAUAUUGGAAUGUAAAAUGUUCUUACUAAGAAUCUUUAUGUCAGCUAUUCAACAUUUCCCUACUUUAUAAUUUCUAGCUGCUUUACCAUUUAGCAACUUUAAAUUUUUAUGCAGUUAAUAUGUUUCUUUGGUUUUUAUGUUUUCUGAAUGUCUUUAAUGCACAUUAAUGUAUACUUAGUAGAUACACAUUUACACAUUGAGAAGUGAAGAUAGGUUUGUGUUCUGUGUACAAUUAGGACAUCCAUUAAAAAAGAUUUUUAAAAACUGUGAAUGGGAAAACAUGUUUUUCCUCCUGUCCUAAAAUAGAACCUGAUGACGGGAGGGAGCAUCAGUCAGUCUGGCCUAAAUCAGUGUACUGCGCUUUUGGAUGCGGGCAAAAGUAUUGUCAUGUUGAUUACUUUAUAAUAACGUAUUAAUAUCAUUGGCUCAAACAGUUGUGAUAUAUACCUAGUAAUCAUCGAGGAUCUCAAAGAUAUGCACCAGUUUGAAUAAAUGCUGUUUAAAGAUUAAAUUUUACAAUUCAUUUUAAAUUGUCAUUUUGUGACAAUAUUUCUAAACAACGUCCAUUUUUAAUAACA